GGAAGCGCCUGCGCGCGCUCCUCCGUACGAGAACUAGUUUUGUUCCGUGCCCUCUGGACUGGAACCUUUUGGAGAGAACCCCCGGCAGGACCAACCCCGCACCCGCCAGCACCGCGGCAAUGUCCAGCAAUAGUUUUCCUUACAAUGAGCAGUCCGGAGGAGGGGAGGCGACGGAGCUGGGUCAGGAGGCGACCUCAACCAUUUCCCCCUCGGGGGCCUUCGGCCUCUUUAGCAGCGAUUUGAAGAAGAAUGAAGAUCUAAAGCAAAUGUUAGAGAGCAACAAAGAUUCUGCUAAACUGGAUGCUAUGAAGCGGAUUGUUGGGAUGAUUGCAAAAGGGAAAAAUGCAUCUGAACUGUUUCCUGCUGUUGUGAAGAAUGUGGCCAGUAAAAAUAUUGAGAUCAAGAAGUUGGUAUAUGUUUACCUGGUUCGAUAUGCUGAAGAACAGCAGGAUCUUGCACUCCUGUCCAUAAGCACUUUUCAGCGAGCUCUGAAGGACCCAAACCAACUAAUUCGUGCAAGCGCUUUGAGAGUUCUGUCAAGUAUUAGAGUGCCAAUUAUUGUACCUAUCAUGAUGCUUGCUAUUAAGGAAGCUUCUGCUGACUUAUCACCAUAUGUUAGGAAGAAUGCAGCCCAUGCAAUACAAAAAUUAUACAGCCUUGAUCCAGAGCAGAAGGAAAUGUUAAUUGAAGUAAUUGAAAAACUUCUGAAAGAUAAAAGCACAUUGGUAGCUGGCAGUGUUGUGAUGGCUUUUGAAGAAGUAUGCCCGGACAGAAUAGAUCUGAUUCAUAAAAAUUACCGCAAGCUAUGUAACUUACUAGUGGAUGUUGAAGAGUGGGGGCAGGUUGUCAUAAUCCACAUGCUAACUCGAUAUGCUCGGACACAGUUUGUCAGCCCUUGGAAAGAGGGUGAUGAAUUAGAAGACAAUGGAAAGAAUUUCUACGAAUCUGAUGAUGAUCAGAAGGAAAAGACUGACAAAAAGAAGAAGCCGUAUACUAUGGAUCCAGAUCAUAGACUCUUAAUUAGAAAUACAAAGCCUUUGCUUCAGAGCAGGAAUGCUGCGGUGGUUAUGGCAGUUGCUCAGCUGUAUUGGCACAUAUCACCAAAAUCUGAAGCUGGCAUAAUUUCUAAAUCACUAGUGCGUUUACUUCGUAGCAAUAGGGAGGUGCAGUAUAUUGUCCUACAAAAUAUAGCAACUAUGUCAAUUCAAAGAAAGGGGAUGUUUGAACCUUAUCUGAAGAGUUUCUAUGUUAGGUCAACUGAUCCAACUAUGAUCAAGACACUGAAGCUUGAAAUUUUGACAAACUUGGCAAAUGAAGCCAACAUAUCAACUCUUCUUCGAGAAUUUCAGACCUAUGUGAAAAGCCAGGAUAAACAAUUUGCAGCAGCCACUAUUCAGACUAUAGGCAGAUGUGCAACCAACAUCUUGGAAGUCACUGACACGUGCCUCAAUGGCUUGGUCUGUCUGCUGUCCAACAGGGAUGAAAUAGUUGUUGCUGAAAGUGUGGUUGUUAUAAAGAAAUUACUGCAAAUGCAACCUGCACAACAUGGUGAAAUUAUUAAACAUAUGGCCAAACUCCUGGACAGUAUCACUGUUCCUGUUGCUAGAGCAAGUAUUCUUUGGCUAAUUGGAGAAAACUGUGAACGAGUUCCUAAAAUUGCCCCUGAUGUUUUGAGGAAGAUGGCUAAAAGCUUCACUAGUGAAGAUGAUCUGGUAAAACUGCAGAUAUUAAAUCUGGGAGCAAAAUUGUAUUUAACCAACUCCAAACAGACAAAAUUGCUUACCCAGUACAUAUUAAAUCUCGGCAAGUAUGAUCAAAACUACGACAUCAGAGACCGUACAAGAUUUAUUAGGCAGCUUAUUGUUCCGAAUGUAAAGAGUGGAGCUUUAAGUAAAUAUGCCAAAAAAAUAUUCCUAGCACAAAAGCCUGCACCACUGCUUGAGUCUCCUUUUAAAGAUAGAGAUCAUUUCCAGCUUGGCACCUUAUCUCAUACUCUCAACAUUAAAGCUACUGGGUACCUGGAAUUAUCUAAUUGGCCAGAGGUGGCGCCCGACCCAUCAGUUCGAAAUGUAGAAGUAAUAGAGUUGGCAAAAGAAUGGACCCCAGCAGGAAAAGCAAAGCAAGAGAAUUCUGCUAAGAAGUUUUAUUCUGAAUCUGAGGAAGAGGAGGACUCUUCUGAUAGUAGCAGUGACAGUGAGAGUGAAUCUGGAAGUGAAAGUGGAGAACAAGGCGAAAGUGGGGAGGAAGGAGACAGCAAUGAGGACAGCAGUGAGGACUCCUCCAGUGAGCAGGACAGUGAGAGUGGACGGGAGUCAGGCCUAGAAAACAAAAGAACAGCCAAGAGGAACUCAAAAGCCAAAGGAAAAAGUGAUUCUGAAGAUGGGGAGAAGGAAAAUGAAAAAUCUAAAACUUCAGAUUCUUCAAAUGACGAAUCUAGUUCAAUAGAAGACAGUUCUUCCGAUUCUGAAUCAGAGUCAGAACCUGAAAGUGAAUCUGAAUCCAGAAGAGUCACUAAGGAGAAAGAAAAGAAAACAAAGCAAGAUAGAACUCCUCUUACCAAAGAUGUUUCACUUCUAGAUCUGGAUGAUUUUAACCCAGUAUCCACUCCAGUUGCACUUCCCACACCAGCUCUUUCUCCAAGUUUGAUGGCUGAUCUUGAAGGUUUACACUUGUCAACUUCCUCUUCAGUCAUCAGUGAAAGAAAAGCACUCCAUCUAAAGUUGGGCAAAAAAUGACCGCCAGUUGACACGGCUGAGUGAAGCAGGACCACAACACUCACUCCCCAAAAGCUAACAAAAUGAUCAAACAAGUAGCGCUAAAAAGAAUGACAACCAGAAGUUCACCAGCAACAAUAAAAUAUGGACAGGAAUAGAACUUUAAACAAAGAAAAUGCUAGAACUCUGAAAAAUGGAACGUGUAGAAAUAAACUGAAUAUUCUACUGCAGAAUGUCAUGGCUCCUAAUAGCACAUCCAGCCCUCAGAACAGUACUGAGAAAAGAAGAUGAAUCAACCAGAGUUUAAGCUUCCUCAUUAUGUGUCUGAAUUUGGAAAGAAGUGGACAGAAGACAUCAGAGGAAAAUAAAGAAAACCCCUCAAGAAUUACAACUCCCAUAUAAUGCUGUGAGAUCUCAACAAGUCUAGGAGCUUUUUUGGAUCCUGAAAUGAAGUUCAUAGAUGAUAGAGUACAUCUAUAAUUUUAAAGUCAACAUGUUGUCCUAGUUGAAUAGAAAAAAUAAAAGUAAUAUAUAAUAAACUAAUAUUUUCAAUGAUAUGUAACUGUUUGACCAUGACUACACUAGAAGUAGUUAAAUGAUGCUGGCACUCGUAUAUAGAACUCAUGAAUGUGAGAACUAUAUGUGCAGAUUGAUAUAGGUGUGUUAUUCGGCAACGCAAAUGCUACGGGUUGUGGUAUUUCCAUCAGUGACAUAAUUUUCCAAACACUGAACAGUUUUUCUGCACCAAAGUACUUGCAUCCCUGGAAAAUUGAGCCUGUUAAAAUCUUGCCAAAGAAAAAAAAAACUUCGUAUUUUAUAUGAAAUGUUCUAGGAUUGAGUAAUUUUAAGCACGUUGUCCAACGUGUUUAACGUGUCUAAUGAGACAGUUGAAUGUUAAUAGUUUCAUUUUCUCAUAGUAGGAAACAGAGCUUUUGUGAGGGACAUGGUACAGUCUGUAUCGUCAGGAUCUGCCCUAUUCAUUACUACGAACAUCUAGCAUUCCUGGCCUUCACUCCUUAAAGCUAGUGGCAUCUUUUACUGUCCCUCCCUCCGGUUGUGUUCUAGUUGUAAACGUCAAAGCAUUAUGUAGCAGUGAAAACCACAGGCUCUUGAUUCAGACCACCUGUGUUCAAGUCAGAGUUCUGCGCUUUACAAAUUAGAGACUUCGGGCAAGCCAGUUUACCUCCCAGUGCCUCCAUUAUUUUCAUCUGUAAAAUGAUCAUGCUACCUACCUCAUAGGAUUGUUGUUGGUAUUAAAUGAUUAACAAACAUGAAAUGUUUAUGACAGUACCUGAUAUGUACUAAUAACUAAAUAUUUCCUGUUAUCAUUUUCAUUACACGUACAUCAUUAGUGCAGCUUUAUAAAGGAAAUGAAGUGUGACCCAAGAAAACUGUGUUUUCUUCUUACUAUUAAGGCUGUACAUAGAUAUGCUGAAACAUGAAAAUUACUAUGGAUUCUACUUUAAAGAAAAAAGAGUGGGGAUACUGCUGAUUGUUGAAACCAAGGAAAGGGUGAUUCAAAGUAAUAGAAUCAGUAGCUAUAAAAAUUGUGAUCAUGUGAUUGAGUAUAAAUGAUAAAAAUAAGAAACCAAAACUAGAAGGUGGGGAAAGAUGACAGGAUGCAUGGUAAUUAUUUUUUCGAUGUAGGUAGGAAAACACUCCGUAAUAUGCAAAAUUGAAACCGCUUUUGUUUUUGUUUUUAAUGAAAUGCAAACCUCUUAAUGAUUUGUAUAUACUCAAAGAACAUCUAUCUGAUGUUUUGGAGGGUUUUUUAUUUUUUGGUUUUAAUUCCAUUUCUUUUUCUUCAAAGUAAGAUUAUAGUCCCAUUCUAAGGGAUAAUUUGUCUGUUUCUCUGUGUAUCUGUCAGUGGUUACAGAAAUGUCACGUUCACCAUGGUUAACAGUUACUUUAGAUGGAAUGGUUUCAGAAUGACUUGUUGAUUGUUUUGGUUCUUUUCUGUAAUGUUUAAAUGUUUUAUAAUAAUAUAAUGAUAACUUUUUAAAACAAAUUAUUACUAUAAAAAUGAGCAAAAGGACUAGAACUGGAAAAAUUAAUUUAUGGUAUAACAAAUCAGAAUAGUGCUUACUCGUAGGAGAAUUAGUGCUUAUAAGGAAAUACAAGAGUAGCUUCUGGGGUGCUGAUAAUGUUCUGUCUUUUGAUCUGGGGGCUGUUACAUGGGUGUAUUCAGUUUAUGAAAAAUAUCAUUGAGCUUUGCACUUAAGAUAUGUGUACUUUAUGUAUAUUCUACUUCAAUAAAAUAUUUUUAAAAGUGGACAAAUGAUAUAAACACAUUAUUCAUAGAGGAGGAAAUAUAGAUGAUAAUAUGCGAAAAAGGUUCAGUGGUAGUAAUGAAAAAAUGUAGAAUUAAAGAACCAUCUUGCCUGUAACAUUAGCAAAAAUUACAAAAACCAACAUCUGUUGUUGCUGAGGUAUGCAAUGAAGCAGGCAUUAUACACUGCUCCACUGGUAAAAGUAUAAAUUAUGACAUCAUUCUGGAUGGCAGUUGGGCCAUCUGUAUAAAAAGCCAUCAAAAUAUGUAUACCUUUUGACCAGGUAAUCUCAUGUCUAGAUUCUUCUUCUAAGGAAAUAAUUAGAAUUACACAGAUUUAUGUGCAUGGUUGUUCAAACCUAAAUGUCUAGUGAUAGUAGUGAUGGUUACAAAAAGUAUGCAAAAACAAUUUAAGGAAUUUUGUACAAUUAUUAAGAUGUUUUUAUUACAUAUUUUAAUAAGAUAAAAUAUGGUAUAAUGUCAGAUGGAAAAAAGGAUACAAAAUGUUAUAUAUAUAAUCUAAAUUUUGUAAAAUUGUACAAUUGUACUGUUUUCAAAUACAAGGAAAUUGAAAGAGUAGAAGAAACUGCAUCAUAAUUUUAACAGCUUUUCUGAAUGAUGAGAUUAUGGAUGUUUUAUAUUUAAUUUUCUUCUGCAUAUUUUUAAAUAUUUUCCAGAUUUUCUCUAAUCAAGAUGUAAUACAUCUAUUACCCAAAAAGCAAUACUUGUAAAAUAGAAAUGGAAAGCACAUAUAUGAAUGACGAGGAUUCCUUUUUAUUUGUUUGGGUCUUUUUCCUUUCCUUUUCCUUUUCCUCUUCCUUUUCUCUUCUUUUCUUUUUUUUUUUUUUUUUUUUUUUUUGACAGGGUCUGGCUCUGUCGCCCAGGUUGGAGUACAUUGGUGUGAUCUUGGCUCACUGCAACCUCUGCUUCCUGGGUUCAAGCCAUCCUUCUACCUCAGCCUCCUGAGUAGCUGGGACUACAGCCACCUGCCACCACACCCUAAUUUUUAUAUUUUUGUUGGUAGAUAUGGCUAAUUUAUUGGCUAAUUUUUUAAUUUUUGUUGGUAGAGCUAGGGUUUCACCAUGUUGCCCAGGCUGGUCUCAAACUCCUGGGCUCAAGUGAGCCACCACACUCAACCAGAUUCCUUUUUAUUGACCCAUCUGAUAUCUGUCUUUCUAGAUCACCACUACUAAUUAAUUGGGUGAUAUUGAGCAAAUCACUUGGUUUUUUUUCAACUAUGAAAUGAUAGCAAGGCAGAUUUCCAUGUUUCCUUUUAACUCUGAUAUUCUAUGUGUGUAUGAACCUAAGAUGGAAUUUCAAAUUAAUGAAAAUAAUUUCACUGGGAUAAUUUGAAUAAGUUUGUUAAAAUAAAGAGAUGAAACUUUUUUAGUUUAAAUGAUGACUUUCUAGUCCAUCUAUAAUUUUUAUUUAUUCUAGUAAAUGUUAUUUGUUUUCCUUAUGUAUAUUAGAUUUUUUCAAUUAACAAAAUAUUUACAGUGAAACCCAAAGAACAAUUGCUUUUUCACAGCAAAUAUUUUUCUAAUUAAAAAAGUCACUAUUUGUUCCUAUCCUUUUAAUUAUAUAUUCAGAACACAGAGAUUUUAAAAAAUAAUGCCUGACAAACAUUAUUAUCAUUAUAAGGAAAGGCUUUAGUUUUUUUAAUAACUCUAUAAUAAAUAUUAUUUAUAAACACAGCAUGUUUUAGUCUUGCCAGAGACUGGCCAUUGGCCAACAGAUAGCUCUAUUGAGGGAACAUUUUAUUUCCUGCUGUAGUAUCUGAGUGAACAAACCGGUUAACUUAGUAAAUUUUUUUUAAUGGAUUAUUAUUUGGUCCUGAGUUUAAAUCAAGACCUGCAAACACAUAAACAUCAAUCCUUAAAAUGUAUGCUUCUUGCAGGGAUGAAAAAAGAAUAGGGGGAAAAAAGACAAUUUUGUGUGUAAGAAUAAAUGUGAAAUAAGAAUAACUUGUUCACCUCUGGUAUUAGAAAUGUUGAGUGAAACUUUGAUCUGUUGUGCUUUAAAUUACUUUGUAUAUUUGGGUCACAAAAAUUUUAAGUGAAUAAAACAGUUAAAGUUAA